CUCUUUCCGCCAUCUUUCCGCGCCGGUGAGUAGCACUCUCUGAGAGCUCCAAUUUCAUCCGUCUGCCAUCGGCGCCAUCCUGCAAUCUAAGCCACAAUGGUGCGCAUGAAUGUCCUGGCAGAUGCUCUCAAGAGUAUCAACAAUGCCGAAAAGAGAGGCAAACGCCAGGUGCUUAUUAGGCCGUGCUCCAAAGUCAUCGUCCGGUUUCUCACUGUGAUGAUGAAGCAUGGUUACAUUGGCGAAUUUGAAAUCAUUGAUGACCACAGAGCUGGGAAAAUUGUUGUGAACCUCACAGGCAGGCUAAACAAGUGUGGGGUGAUCAGCCCCAGAUUUGACGUGCAACUCAAAGACCUGGAAAAAUGGCAGAAUAAUCUGCUUCCAUCCCGCCAGUUUGGUUUCAUUGUACUGACAACCUCAGCUGGCAUCAUGGACCAUGAAGAAGCAAGACGAAAACACACAGGAGGGAAAAUCCUGGGAUUCUUUUUCUAGGGAUGUAAUACAUAUAUUUACAAAUAAAAUGCCUCAUGGACUCUGGUGCUUCCACUUGGUCGUUUUGAGCCUUUACAGCAGUGUAGCCACAGCUUCUGCGGCAGCAUGCAGUUGCUUCGUUUAUCGGUGAAUGCGAUUCCCUGAAGUGACUAAUACAGCCAAGGGAAAAAGUUCUUAUGAAACCAGUAUGCCUAAGAAACAGUCACCCCUGCUGUCUGCCAAAACCAGGUAUUUGACACUAAAUAUUUUAGUUGUAUUUCAGUUUUUUUUUUUUUUUUUCUUUUUUGGAGACAGAGUCUGACUCUAUUGCUCAGGCUGGAGUGCAGUGGCGCGAUCUUGGCCCACUGCAACCUCCACCUCCCGGGUUCAAGUGAUUGUCCUGUCUCAGCCGCCUGAGUAACUGGGAUUACAAGUGUGUGUCGCCACAUCCGGCUAAUUUUUAUAUUUUAGUAGAGACAGGGUUUCGCCAUGUUGCCCAGGCUGGUCUUGAGUUCUGGGCCUCAAGUGAUCAGCCUACCUCGGCCUCCCGAAGUGCUGGGAUUACAGCCACGAGCCAUUACACCUGGCCUAUAUUUCAGUAUUUUCUAUUAGUUUUUGAUGAAUUUGUUUUGCCUGGCUAGGAUUAUUCUGUAGAUAGGAUUUUAGAUCUGGCUUUUGUCACUGACUGCUGUAAUAAAUACUUGCUAGGAAUUUUUUUUUUUUUUUUUUUUUUUUUAAGACAAAGUCGCUCUGUCACACAGGCUGGAGUGCAGUGGCAUGAUCUUGGCUCACUGCACCUCCGCUUCCCAGAUUCAAGUAGUUCUCGUGCCUCAGCCUCCUGAGUAGCUGGGAUUACAGGUGUGUGCCACCAUGUCUGGCUGAUUUUUGUAUUUUUAGUAGAGGUGGGGUUUCACCAUGUUGGCCAGGCUGGUCUCGAACUCCUGAUCUCAAGUGAUCUGCCUGCCUUGGUCUCCCAAAGUGCUGGGAUUACAGGUGUGACCACCACGCCCUGCCUUAAGAAUUGUUCCAAGAGAAUCUGGUGCCACUUGCAGGUGCCCAUUGAAGUGCAAUGGGCACUGUUGAUCACUGAGGAGGUAGUGGGUGCUGACCCGGUGCUGGGGCCUGUCCCCUAGUCUCUGCUUUGCCCUUGGCUAGCUAGGUGGUGUGCCAAGUGGGGAGAGAAGCUACCUUAUUAAGGGGCAUGGAUCAGCUUCCUGAAAGGAGGGCCUGCCUCUGUAAGAUAUGGGAAGUCGCUGAGAAUGUUACAGAACGGCCCUAGAGAUGGGGCAGAUAACGGCCCCCAUUUGUGAGAAGUGAGUUGGGAGGCAUGUUUGGGGCCUCUGAUGUUUGGGAGGCUGUGGGUAAUUAACAUGAGUUUUGGGGUCCAGCAGCAGAAUUCAGGUUUCCUCUUCCACUCAGUAACCUCAGCAUCCGUAUCUGUAAUGGGAAUGAUACAAAACCUAUCCCCAAGUUGAGGGAAAAAUGAGAUUGUGUAAAGCGCACUUGGCACAUGACAGUCACAAGCAUGGGGACAGUGAGUCCAGAAGGAUUUUCUUAUGCCAGCAUUGUAAGCCCUAGGAUCACAGGGCUCUGGCUUGUUUAACCAUCGUGUCUCUGGUCCCUAGCCUGCAAACCUGGUGUGUAGGGAUGCCUCAGUCGCUUACAUGUUGAUUGAGUGAAUCGUCGGUUUCUUUCUGGACACUGACUUCAAAAAUAAAAUAGGAUAUGAAAAUGG